GUUUCCUGGCCGAGGUGGGUCGGUAGUAGCGAUGGCGGGUCUGACUGACUUGCAGCGGCUACAGGCCCGAGUGGAAGAGCUGGAGCGCUGGGUGUACGGGCCGGGCGGGGCGCGCGGCUCACGGAAGGUGGCUGACGGCCUGGUCAAGGUGCAGGUGGCUUUGGGGAACAUUUCCAGCAAGAGGGAGAGGGUGAAGAUUCUCUACAAAAAGAUUGAAGAUCUGAUCAAGUACCUGGAUCCUGAGUACAUCGACCGCAUUGCCAUACCUGAUGCCUCUAAGCUGCAAUUCAUCCUAGCAGAGGAGCAGUUUAUCCUUUCCCAGGUUGCACUCCUGGAGCAGGUGAAUGCCUUGGUGCCCAUGCUGGACAGUGCUCACAUCAAAGCCGUUCCUGAGCAUGCUGCCCGCCUGCAGCGCUUGGCCCAGAUCCACAUUCAGCAGCAGGCUCCAUGGGGAGUGGGAGUCCGUGAUGAGGCAGGAAGUUUAGUGGAAGAUGUGGGCUUUGCCCAGUUCCUUUCUGUGCUACACUUUGGCCCUACAGGACCAGUGUGUGGAAAUCACUGAGGAGUCCAAGGCUCUCCUGGAGGAAUACAACAAGACUACAAUGCUUCUCUCCAAGCAAUUCGUGCAGUGGGAUGAGCUACUUUGCCAGCUAGAGGCCGCCACGCAAGUGAAGCCAGCAGAGGAGUGAUAGCUGCUCCCCAUCCCAAAGUGGGCCUGGGCAGUCAGGCUCCAGGGCCCUAUGCCAACCUGCCUUUGUUACAAGGCAGAGGAAGCUUUGUAUUUAUUGGCUUCAAGGCCCACCUCUCUGUACUCUGGGCUCUAAAGUUGGAGGUCAGGUUACCUGAGGUUUGCAAUUUGCAACACCCACCCUCCCCCCAAUCAGUGUUCUUAUUUCAGUGACAAUAAACCAUAGAGAUGACUGGA